ACCAGUCAUCAAGCGAGGCUCGCGCGCAGGCCCCGCGUUGGAAAAUGGCGGGGAAGCUGAAACCUCUGAAUGUGGAGGCGCCAGAAGCUACUGAGGAGGCUGAAGGGCAAGCCAAGUCUUUGAAGACUGAAGACUUGCUGGCAAUGGUGAUAAAGCUGCAGAAAGAGGGAAGCCUGGAGCCACAGAUAGAGGACCUGAUUAGCCGGAUUAAUGAUCUUCAGCAAGCAAAGAAGAAAUCCAGUGAGGAACUGAGAGAGACCCACAGUCUCUGGGAGGCCCUGCAUAGGGAAUUAGACUCCUUGAAUGGAGAGAAAGUGCACCUAGAGGAGGUCUUGGGCAAAAAGCAAGAGGCACUGAGGAUCCUCCAGAUGCACUGCCAAGAGAAGGAAAGCGAGGCUCAGAGGUUGGAUGUCAGAGGACAGCUGGAGGAUCUGAUGGGCCAGCACAAGGACCUCUGGGAAUUCCACAUGCUGGAGCAGCGACUGGCCCGGGAGAUCCGUGCCCUGGAGAGAAGCAAGGAGCAGCUGCUCUCGGAGAGGAGGCUGGUGCGCGCCAAGCUGCGGGAGGUGGAGCGGCGGCUGCACUCGCCGCCUGAGGUCGAGGGCGCCAUGGCGGUGAAUGACGGGCUGAAGGCGGAGCUGGAGAUAUUCGGGGAGCAGGUCCGGAGCGCCCCCGAGGUCGGGGCCGGCGAGGGAGAGGCCGGACCUGAGCUCCCCCGCGCUCGCGACGAGGAGGAUCCCGAGCCGCCGGUGGCUGCCCCUGACGCCCUCUAGGCCAGCAGGACCCGCCCGUUCCCGACCUUCCCUCGAGACCCGCCAAGAAAUAAAGGCGAUGAUUUCCGACCAUGCUCGCGUUCUCCGCGGAGUCUGUGCUACACCGUGGAGCGGGGCGGGGCGUGCUGGGAUCUCGAGGCGGGGCCUCUGCCGGACCCCUCCCACCAGUCGAGCCCCGGGCGCCGUACAGAGGCUGGGUAAAUGCUCCUGAACUCAGAGAGAGUAAGUGGGUGUCAGUAUCCCCCGCCCCACGGCCUCAUCUCGAGUUCCCAAACCAUCUAUGU